CUUUUCUCAAAGACCUUGCCGCUCAACUGGAUCCAGGCCCUUGCAUCUUGGCGGAUCUGAGGCGUUUGGAGGGACAACAACCUAGAUGUGGAGCCGAAAUUUGAGGGUGUGACCUAUCUUAUGCGGAGCGGACCUUUGAGGAUCUCUGAGUGGAAGGUGUACUACAAAUUCUUGCAAUCCUCACGCUCUUCGUCUGCGGCGACAGUUCACCUGGGGUGGGCCUGAUUUGUUCCUGACUCUAGCAAACAAACCCCGGGACCGGGGAGAGCUGGGAUGUUGGAGCGCCCUGAGGCCAGGCUACUUGGGGGCAAACUGAGGAAAGAGUGUUGAGGAUUAUUUCUAGAGUUCAAAGGUCAGAGGUCAAUGUAGCGAGGAGUUGUGGGGGAGUCCAAAGUCGGAGGGGUGCUUAGGGGAGAAUUAGGGAGGGACUGAAUACUCAAGGGACAGAUUUGUGGAUAAGUAGCUUGGAGGGAGGAGAAACCGGGAGGGGGCAGAUGGCGUAGUGCUGGGGAGGCGGGGACACAGGGGAAGAGAGAGGGGGAAAGGAAUCCCCUGAAUAUUCAUUCCCAGACUUCAGGCCUGUCAGUCGCAGUCUCGGUCGUACCUCCCCUAGUUGCAACCUUAGCUGUUGGCAGGGUGAAGAGAUGGCUUCCCCGUCUAGACAGCCCCCGCCAGGGGGGUCAGGACUGCUUCAAGGGAGCCGGGCUCGUUCAUAUGGAAGCCUGGUGCAAUCGGCCUGCUCCCCAGUGAGGGAAAGACGCCUGGAGCAUCAGUUGGAGCCCGGAGACACCCUGGCUGGACUAGCACUCAAAUAUGGGGUGACGAUGGAACAGAUUAAACGUGCAAACCGCCUUUAUACUAAUGACUCCAUCUUCCUGAAGAAAACCCUCUACAUCCCCAUCCUGACAGAGCCCAGAGACCUGUUCAAUGGUUUGGACUCUGAGGAAGAGAAAGAUGGAGAGGAAAAAGUACACCCAAGUAACAGUGAAGUUUGGCCACACUCAACUGAGAGGAAGAAACAAGAGACAGGAGCAGGACGUGCCAAUGGUGAAGUCCUCCCCACACCUGGCCAGGAAACCCCCACGCCCAUCCAUGACCUCUCUGCCUCUGAUUUCCUUAAGAAGCUUGAUUCACAGAUCAGCCUGUCCAAGAAGGCUGCUGCUCAGAAGCUGAAAAAAGGGGAAAAUGGGGUACCUGGGGAGGAUGCAGGUCUCCACCUGAGCUCCCCUUGGAUGCAGCAACGAGCAGUCCUAGGUCCUGUGCCGCUGACCCGUACCUCUCGGACCCGGACACUACGGGACCAGGAGGAUGAAAUCUUCAAACUCUGAUGUCCCCAGAACUGACUGAGAGAAGCAAGAUGUUGAAAGAGAAACUUCAGGGGGAGAGGAGCCUGAGGAUGUGGCUGUGACCGCAGUGAGGAGCAGCCUCGCCCUCUCCCCCAAACCAAAAUGGGAGUCUGAAGAGGCAGAGGAGGUGGAGACUGUGGGGGUUUUUUUCCCCAGCUGAAUCCUUCCAGUGGAAACCUGAACCUUGCUUUGCUCCCAGCUUGCCUUGGGGCUUUCUGGACCAUGCUCCCCAGCCGGAAGAGGAGAUUGCUCCAUUUCCUGAAGAUCCUGUCCUUACAUUUCUACAGUACUGGGAAGGAUGUAAAGCCCAAAUUUCUGGGGUAGGAGGCACUAUGCUACAAGGAAAGGAUACAGUGUUGAGCAAGAUAGACAACCAGGGACUGCAUACAACUUACAGUAAAGUCAUAGGUGAACCUUCGACAGGUGAUACGGAUGGCAUUCACUAGGAUGAGAGAGACAUGAUGCAGGUAAGUAUAUCUGUAGGGAGCAAAAAGUUGGUGGAAUUCUCACUUUAUUAUCUCUGUUUUCUCUGAAGACGGAUGAGGGUUUUCCUGAGAUGAACAAGGAAAUGGUAAGGAAAGGAACUUGCAAAAAAAGGAGGAAGUUUGAAAUAUCUCCCUGGGGAUUGGAAGAGAGUGCUUUUCCAAUCCAAUCUGUGGGACUGUGUGAUUUCCUUUUUUUGAGAUGGAGUCUCGCUCUGUUGCCCAGGCUGGAGUGCAGUGGUGCGAUCUCGGCUCACUGCAAGCUCCGCCUCCUGGGUUCAAGCAAUUCUCCUGCCUCAGCCUCCCCAGUAGUUGGGACUACAGGCGCACACCGCCACGCCCGGCUAAUUCUUUUUAUUUUAGUAGAGACGGGGUUUCACUGUUGUUGCCCAGGCUGGUCUCGAACUCCUGAGCUCAGGCAAUCCACCCGCCUCAGCCUCCCAAAGUGCUAGGAUUACAGGCCUGAGUCACUGCGCCCGGCCAGGACUGUGUGAUUUUCUUCAAAACACUAAGGGAGUAGGAAGAGAGGUUUUUUAUUUUUAUUUUUAUUUUUUUAAGAGUCUCCCUCUGUGUCACCCAGGCUGGAGUGCAGUGGCACGAUCUUGGCUCACUGCAAUCUCCUGUCACCUGAGUUCAAGCAAUUCCCCUGCCUCAGCCUCCUGAGUAGCUGGGAUUGCAGGUGCCCAUCACCACACCCGGCUAAUUUUUUUUUGUAUUUUUAGCAGAGCUGGAGUUUCUCCAUGUUGGCCAGGCUGGUCUCAGAACUCCUGACCUCAGGUGAUCUGCCCACUUCGGCCUCCCAAAGUGCUGGGAUUACAGGGGUGAGCCACCUCGCCCAGCCAAGAGAGUCAUUUUGAUUUGUCCUUCAAAAUAGCUCUCAGAUUCAUGUAUUUCUUUCUAAAUCUGUUCCCAUCACCCUUGUCUGAUUGUCCCUCUCCCCUCACCUUUAAACCUUGUUUACUUGCUAGUAGGUCUCUGUCUUCUUGCUUAAAAAAAUAAAAAAAUACAAGUUGCACCCUUUUUCAAGAAUUUAAAAUGACGUCCUACUCCUGUCAGAUGAUUUUAACCAGCUCACCUAGUCAUUCCAGGCCUUCUGUAAUUUGUCUUCCCCUUUUCCCUCCCCUUGCUCCUAACUAGUGCCUUUCCCACACACCAGCCUCACAGGACCUUUUUUUUAUCCAUGCUGCAGGCUCCUUGCUAACCAAGUAAAAGCUUUUGCUGAAGCUGUGUCCCUCGGGAACAUUUUCUUCUUUUGCACCAAGCCAACUCCCACCAAAGUUUUCCUGUCCUUCAUGAUAAAAUGUAUCCAGCAUCUUUCUGUGCAGUCUUCGGAGAAUAUUUAUUGUCUUCUUUGCACAUUUGGAAAUUUAUGUUCAAUGUAGCUUUUCUUUUGAGACUUGGUGUUGUCUUUUUAAUAGUUUAGUACUAUUAAAUAUUUAAUAUUUAGUACUGUC